AUAUCCUUCUCAGACUUGGAUCAGGUGAAGUACUGAUCGUGACUGCUCCAUAACAUCCGGCACCAUGAUCUUAAACACGCGUGGGAUUGAGAGCUACUAUACAUAACCCCAGAGGUCUCCUCUAAUCCUGUUGCUCCUUGGUUUUAGAAUCCAGAAUCCUCAUGUUAAGGAAUGUGGGUGGUUUGAAGUCAGAAAAAUGGGUAAGAAGAGUCGAGUAAAAACUCAGAAAUCUGGCACUGGUGCUACAGCAACUGUGUCACCAAAGGAAAUCUUGAACCUGACCAGUGAGCUGCUGCAGAAAUGCAGCAGUCCGGCGCCUGGCCCAGGAAAAGAGUGGGAAGAGUAUGUGCAGAUCCGGACUCUGGUUGAGAAAAUACGGAAAAAGCAAAAAGGUCUGUCCGUUACUUUUGAUGGAAAAAGAGAAGAUUACUUUCCUGAUCUAAUGAAAUGGGCCUCUGAAAAUGGGGCUUCUGUCGAGGGUUUUGAAAUGGUUAACUUCAAAGAAGAGGGCUUUGGUUUGAGAGCAACAAGAGAUAUCAAGGCAGAAGAAUUGUUUUUAUGGGUUCCACGAAAAUUGCUAAUGACUGUUGAAUCUGCUAAAAAUUCAGUGUUGGGGCCCUUAUAUUCUCAAGACCGAAUCCUUCAAGCCAUGGGAAACAUCGCACUGGCCUUUCAUUUGCUGUGUGAGCGAGCCAGCCCUAACUCCUUCUGGCAGCCCUAUAUUCAAACCCUCCCCAGUGAAUAUGACACUCCUCUCUACUUUGAAGAAGAUGAAGUUCGGUAUCUUCAGUCCACACAAGCUAUACAUGAUGUCUUCAGCCAGUAUAAAAACACAGCUCGACAGUACGCCUACUUCUAUAAAGUCAUCCAGACCCAUCCUCAUGCCAACAAACUACCCUUGAAGGAUUCUUUCACUUACGAGGACUACAGGUGGGCAGUCUCUUCUGUUAUGACGAGGCAAAACCAAAUUCCCACAGAGGAUGGUUCCCGCGUGACCCUGGCUCUGAUUCCUUUAUGGGAUAUGUGUAACCACACCAACGGCCUGAUCACUACUGGUUACAACCUGGAAGAUGACCGCUGUGAGUGUGUGGCUCUGCAGGAUUUUCGGGCUGGAGAGCAGAUUUACAUUUUUUAUGGCACUCGAUCCAACGCAGAGUUUGUGAUCCACAGUGGUUUUUUCUUUGACAAUAACUCACACGACAGAGUGAAAAUAAAGCUUGGAGUGAGUAAAAGUGACAGACUCUACGCCAUGAAGGCCGAGGUCUUGGCUCGUGCCGGCAUCCCCACUUCCAGUGUUUUUGCAUUGCAUUUUACCGAGCCGCCCAUCUCUGCUCAGCUUUUGGCUUUUCUCCGAGUAUUCUGUAUGACUGAAGAAGAACUGAAAGAACACUUGCUGGGAGACAGCGCUAUUGAUAGAAUCUUCACCUUGGGGAACUCGGAAUUUCCUGUUAGCUGGGACAACGAGGUCAAACUUUGGACAUUUCUUGAAGAUAGAGCCUCACUUCUUUUAAAAACAUAUAAAACAACUAUUGAGGAAGAUAAAUCCGUCUUGAAAAACCACGAUCUUUCUGUUCGUGCAAAAAUGGCCAUCAAAUUGCGCUUAGGUGAGAAAGAGAUUUUGGAAAAAGCAGUAAAGAGUGCAGCUGUCAACCGGGAAUACUAUCGCCAACAGAUGGAGGAAAAGGCUCCGCUUCCCAAAUAUGAAGAGAGUAACCUUGGGCUGUUGGAGAGCAGCGUGGGGGACUCGAGGCUCCCCCUGGUCUUGAGAAACCUCGAGGAGGAGGCUGGAGUGCAGGAUGCCUUGAACAUCAGAGAGGCAAUCAGCAAAGCAAAGGCCACAGAAAACGGGCUUGUAAACGGUGAAAACUCUAUCCCUAAUGGGACCAGGUCCGAAAAUGAAAGUCUCAAUCAAGAAAGUAAAAGAGCAGUUGAAGACGCCAAAGGAUCUUCUUCAGACAGCACUGCUGGAGUUAAGGAGUAGCUCGAGGUGAAGCUGGAUGGGGGAUCCAGUGGAGCAGGAGUUGACGGACAGUCCGUUCACAUCGCUGUGUUUCCUUGUUAACAUUUUUCUUUCUGCAGAGAGGAAGAUAUGUUUUUGCUGCUUUAUAUAAAAAUGGUUUUUUUAAGUUAUUUUAAAAAUCUAGCUUCCCUUUUUGAUUAAGAUUGCCAUCUUGCUUUUAGGCAAAACAAACCAAUUAACAAACAACCACAAGAAAGGGAGAAGAGGUGCCUGUGGGAGAUUUUGCAGACCUAUUGUGGGUAUAGGUAUUUUCUUCCUGGGGAAGAAUUCAGUUCCCGUCUCAGCUGUACUUUUGUGGGCCUGUCAUCUUGAUGACCAGAAUGAAAGCUUGCUCUGCCUCCUGCCAGCCAGAAUUGGUGGCGGGACUUGGGGAUACAGCGUGAAGGUGGGGAAGUUGCACAGCAGAAAACAGAAUUGAAGUUGGGAAACUCUAGAGUCUGGGCAAAAUGUUUGGUUUUUUCUCUUAAAAAAAAUAACACCCCAUUACCAAAAGAAAAGGUAAGGUGGCAACCUUAUUUUUAAUAGUUUGAAAUGAUGAUAAUCCUAAUUAUAUAAAAAUAUAUAUAUAAACACACAUAUAUAUAGUGAUUUCUAAAGAUUUGUUUACUUUUGUGUUUUGUUUUACUGUACUAAGAACUUGUCCUUUCUCCUUGAAUCAAAGUAGGACAUGCAUCAUCCUCCUAAUUUUAAAUGUUGGCUCUGAUUUUAAAGUGGUGCAUUUGAUUCCAGCCUUGGUAAUGGAGAGUUUGCAAACACACAGCGGCCCACAGCUUCACGUGGUGGUGUGCAGUGUGAGGCAGCUCCUUGGCUUUCCUGGUUUUCACAACAAGCUAGAGAUUUUCAAAGCUACACUUUUGAGUAAAAACCCUUAUUAAAAGAAAAACAUGAUUAA